CCUUGCAGCUCUCCUCAGCGCGCUGCUCCCACUCGCAAUCAAAAGGCGGAAAAAGCGCGAAACCGCCAGGCAUCUCCCAUACCCACCCGGCUGCCGCGCAACCCCUCCUUGGCUUCCACUGGGAGACAGGGGACGCCGAUGAGCAGGAAGAAGCAGGGCAGUGACUGCUUAGUUUAUCCUGGUCACCCGCCAGGUUUGUGGCCUGUGAUCUCUUGUCACCUUGGUCUCUCAGCUUUGUCUUCUGAAAUCUGGACUUCCAAUUGUCUUUGUCUUGCUGCCCUUCCUUGCGACACUGGCCUGGAAUCCCUCACGGUAGUCUGCUGGAGUGGAAUUUAGGACGCAUCUCAGUUGUCACCAUCUUUAAUUGCAUGAUGUCUAGUUCCUUGCAAACCAUUAUUUCAUGUAUUUCGCUCUUUUUUGUUUGUUUUGUUUUGUUUUGUUUUCAGGCUAGGGGAAAAUCCAGUCCCUGUUACUCCAUUUUGGCCAGAAAUUCAAGAUGGUGUCACAAGAAGGAUCUGAAGUGGAGCUUCUAGUAUCCCCAGGAGCGCGAAGUGAACACGGAAGGUACCUGCAGGAUCCAAUUGUGUCCAUUGAUCUCUCAGAGUGGCUGAGGAUAAUAGAGUUUCUUCUUCAAGGUCUCAAGGUCUGAAGCAUCCCACAGAAUGAUCCUACUGAAUAACUCCCAUAAGCUGCUGGCCCUAUACAAAUCCUUGGCCAGGAGCAUCCCUGAGUCCCUGAAGGUGUAUGGCUCUGUGUAUCACAUCAAUCACGGGAACCCCUUCAACAUGGAGGUGCUGGUGGAUUCCUGGCCUGAAUAUCAGAUGGUUAUUAUCCGGCCUCAAAAGCAGGAGAUGACUGAUGACAUGGAUUCAUACACAAACGUAUAUCGUAUGUUCUCCAAAGAGCCUCAAAAAUCAGAAGAAGUUUUGAAAAAUUGUGAGAUCGUAAACUGGAAACAGAGACUCCAAAUCCAAGGUCUUCAAGAAAGUUUAGGUGAGGGGAUAAGAGUGGCUACAUUUUCAAAGUCAGUGAAAGUAGAGCAUUCGAGAGCACUCCUCUUGGUUACGGAAGAUAUUCUGAAGCUCAAUGCCUCCAGUAAAAGCAAGCUUGGAAGCUGGGCUGAGACAGGCCACCCAGAUGAUGAAUUUGAAAGUGAAACUCCCAACUUUAAGUAUGCCCAGCUGGAUGUCUCUUAUUCUGGGCUGGUAAAUGACAACUGGAAGCGAGGGAAGAAUGAGAGGAGCCUGCAUUACAUCAAGCGCUGCAUAGAAGACCUGCCAGCAGCCUGUAUGCUCGGCCCAGAGGGAGUCCCGGUCUCAUGGGUAACCAUGGACCCUUCUUGUGAAGUAGGAAUGGCCUACAGCAUGGAAAAAUACCGAAGGACAGGCAACAUGGCACGAGUGAUGGUGCGAUACAUGAAAUAUCUGCGUCAGAAGAAUAUUCCAUUUUACAUCUCUGUGUUGGAAGAAAAUGAAGACUCCCGCAGAUUUGUGGGGCAGUUUGGUUUCUUUGAGGCCUCCUGUGAGUGGCACCAAUGGACUUGCUACCCACAGAAUCUAGUUCCAUUUUAGACAAUGAAGCUGCUUAGUAAUCUCUGCCAAGCCAUCUCUUAAUAUUAAAGCAGACACCACAGAAUAGAUUUCUUCACUUACAAAUGCAUAUUGGGCACUUAUAAUACAGCAGGAACUCUUCUCACCUGGAGCCUUGAUGUUAAAAGACACAGCCAUGCUCUUGAGGAGCUUACAAUCCUGGCUGGAGGCAGGGGAGGGUAUAUUCUUUAAAUAUGCUUAAGUGUUAUAGGGAAAGACGGGGUUACCAGUAAACAUGUAACUAGAAAGCCAGGCUCAGUUCUUACCUCUGGGAAUCAGAACUCUUUAUGCAACUUGGUUAAUAGAAUCUACUAUCUGGAAGAUAAAUGAAGGAUUUUAAUAAAAUUUUCAAUAGAAUAAA